AGAGCACCGGACGACAACAGCAGCAGCAACAACGCGGCAGCCGCCACCAUGGCCCUGCAGGCUGAUUUUGACAGGGCUGCAGAAGAUGUGAGGAAGCUGAAAGCAAGACCAGAUGAUGGAGAACUGAAAGAACUCUAUGGGCUUUACAAACAAGCAAUAGUUGGAGACAUUAAUAUUGCGUGUCCAGGAAUGCUAGAUUUAAAAGGCAAAGCCAAAUGGGAAGCAUGGAACCUCAAAAAAGGGUUGUCGACGGAAGAUGCGACGAGUGCCUAUAUUUCUAAAGCAAAGGAGCUGAUAGAAAAAUACGGAAUUUAGAAUACAGCAUAUGAGGAAUUUUUCCUUUUGAAGACUUCCAAAUGCUAUCAUGACCUAACAUUUAGAGGGAGAGGCAUACUGUUAACUUGAUGUAUCAUGUAUAUUUUUGCUAUUAGCAUGAGCUGUAGUACUUAGAAGUAUACUGAAACUACAUAGUUAACUCAAUUGUACUUGCUUAAACCAGGUGUCUUUAAAAGUUCUUUUUAAGAAAAUGUGGCACAUAUACACCAUGGAAUACUAUGGAGCCAUAAAAAGGGAUGAGUUCAUGUCCUUUGCAGGGACAUGGAUGAAGCUGGAAACCAUCAUUCUCAGCAAACUAUCACAAGAUCAGAAAACCAAGCAUGUUCUCACUCAUAAGUGGGAGUUGAACAAUGAGAACACAUGGACACAGGGAAGGGAACAUCACACACUGGGGCCUGUCGGGGACUAGGGGGUUAGGGGAGGGAUAACAUUAGGAGACAUACCUGAUGUAGGUGACCGGUUGAUGGGUACAGCAAACCACCAUGGCACAUGUAUACCUAUGUAACAAAACUGCACGUUCUGCAUAUGUAUCCCAGAACUUAAAGUAUAAAAAAAAAAAUUCUUUUAGAAAAGUAUUUUUUAUUUUUAUAGAGUUAGGGAGUACAGUUGCAGUUUUUGUUUGUUUGUUUGUUUUUUCUUGAGGAGUCUCACUCUGUCACCCAGGCUGGAGUGCAGUCGUGUGAUCUCGGUUCACUGCAACCUCCGCCUCCUGGGUUCAAGUGAUUCUCUUGCCUCAGCCUCCCGAGUAGCUGGGAUUACAGGUGCUUGCCACCAUGGCUGGCUAAUUUUUGUAUUUUUAGUAGAGACGGGGUUUUGCCAUGUUGGCCAGGCUGGUCUCGAACUCCUGACCUCAGGUGAUCUGCCCACCUUGGCGCUGGGGUUGCAGGUGUGAGCCACCACACCUGGUCACAGGUGCAGUUUUGUUACAUGGAUAUAUUGUGUAGUGGGGAAAUCUGGGCUUUUAGUGUAACCAUCACCAAAAUACUGUACAUUGUACCCAAAAGGUAAUUGCUCAUCCCUCACCCCCUCCCACCUUUCCAAGCCUCCAGUGUCUAUUAUUCCACACUCCAUGACCCUGUAUACACCCUGUUUAACUCCCACUUAUAAGUGAAAACAUGUGGUAUUUUUUUUUGUUUCUGAGGGUUCUUUAAAAAUCUUUAUUUUCUUAUUUUUUUCUGAGUUGUUUCACUUAAGAUAAUAGCCUCCAGUUCCACCCACGUUGCUGCAAAAGCCGUAAUUUCAUUCUCUUUAUAUGGCUGAGUAAUAUCCCCUGGUAUACAUAUACAACGUUUUCUUUAUCCCAUCAUCUGCUGAUGGAUACUUAGGUUGAUUCCAUAUCUUUGCUCUUGUGAAUUGUGCUGCAAUAGAUAUACAAGUGCAGGUAUCUUUUGGAUAGAAUGAUUUAUUUUCCUUUAAGAAGAUACCCAGUAGUGGGAUUGCUGGGUAGAAUGGUAGUUCUAUUUUUAGUUCCAUGAGAAAUUUCCGUGCUGUUUUUCAUAGAGGUUGUACUAAUUUACAUUCCCACCAAUAGUGUAUAAGCAUUCCCUUUUCUCCACAUCUGUUGUUUUUUGACUUUUUAGAAAGUCUAGCCCUGGUAAUAUGUGUACAGAUUUGAACAGCUGUUUGUUCUUUUGGCUCAUCUGUUCUGUUACAAUAAGUUAAUGUUACUGGUGAAAUAAAAACAGGUUAUUAAGAAUCAAUGGCAAGGCUGAGCGUGGUGGCUCACGCCUCUAAUCUCAGCACUUUGGGAGGCCGAGGUAGGUGGAUUACUGAGGUCAGAAGUUCGAGACCAGCCUGACCAACAUUGCAAAACCCCAUCUCUACUAAAAAUACAAAAAUUAGCCAGCCAUUGGUGGUGCACACCUGUAAUUCCAGCUACUUGGGAGGCUGAGGCAGGAGAAUUGCUUUUACCCAGGAGAUGGAGGUUGCAGUGAGCCAAGAUCACACCACUGCACUCCAGCCUGGGCGACAAAACAAGACUCCGUCUCAAAAAAAAAAAAAAAAAUUACAAGUCUGUCCAUAGCAGUUUAAAGAAAUUUAAAAAGCCCCCAUAGGAAUAUCUAUUUUUCUUUAAAUUUUUACAUUUAAGACAUUUAAGACAAAAAGGCAAACUAAAAUGUAUCUAGUGAUAAACUGUACCACUACUGUACCCCAUAUGUUCAGUUCUAUCUGAGUAAAAAUAGAGUCUGGAAUAUAAUAUUGGCCCCCUACUCAGUCUUUCUGGAUGGUACACAGGCUCUUUGAAAGAAGACAGUCUCAUGUUAACAAUUCAAAAAAUUGUUUGAGAUCCCUUAAGAUAAAUAUCCCCCAAAACAGUGUACCUCUAUUCCCUGCAUAAAAAUUUAGAUUUGGAAUGGUAUGACCAGAGGAAUAGAUCCACUUCAUGUUACUACAACAACAAAACUAUCUAGGUCUGCUAGAUGAAUUUCCAGGGAAUUAUGCUGAGCAGAAAAAGCCAGUCCCCAAAUGUGACAUGUAUAAUUCCAUUUAUAUAACAUUCUUUUUCUUUUCUUUUUUUUUUUUUUUUUUUUUGUUGAGACAGGCUGUCACUCUGUUACCCAGGCUGGAGCGCAGUGGCACGCUCUCGGCUCACUGCAACCUCUGCCUCCCAGGGUCAAGCAAUCCUCCCAUCUCAGCCUCCAGAGUAGCUGGGACUACAGGUGCGUGCAACCAUGCCCAGCUAAUUUUUGUAUUUUUCAUAGAGACAGGGUUUCACCAUGUUGCCCAGGCUGGUCUGGAACUCCUGAUCUGAGGUGAUCUACCCACCUUGGCCCCCCAAAGUGCUGAGACUAUAGGCAUGAGCCACCGCGUCCAGCCAGGAUUCUUGAAAGGGAACAUUUAUAGACGCAAAGGAUGGAAUAGUGGUUGCCAGGGAGGAGGGAGGUGGGUGUGGCUUUAAAAGGGCAGCAGGAGGGAUGAUCCUGCAGUGAUGGAAUGUUCUGUCUUGAUUGUAGCAACACCAAUAUGCUGAUUGUGAUAUUAUACUAUAGUUUUGCAUAACAGUUACCAUUAAAGGAAAUUGGGUAAAAGGCUA